CUGUGCGCGGAGGGCGUGGCCUGUGCGGGGCGGGACUUAUUGCCCGCGCGGUGAGGGAGCGUGGUCUCGCGCAAGCCGGCGUGCGGUCCCGCGGCGCUGCAGUUGUGUCCAGCCGGUCACGGGGCGGCUAUGGCGGCCACGUUCUUCGGAGAGGUGGUGAAGGCGCCGUGCCGAGCUGGGACUGAGGACGAAGAGGAGGAGGAGGAGGGGCGGAGGGAGACGCCCGAGGACAGGGAGGUGCGUCUGCAGCUGGCGCGGAAGAGUUUCAUCUUGUUUCUUGUGUUAGGGAAGUGCGGCUCCUUCGAAGACAAACAAAAACAUCUUUGGAAGUUUCUUUGCUAGAAAAAUAUCCGUGCUCCAAGUUUAUAAUUGCUAUAGGAAAUAAUGCAGUAGCAUUUCUGUCAUCAUUUGUUAUGAAUUCAGGAGUCUGGGAGGAAGUUGGUUGUGCUAAACUCUGGAAUGAAUGGUGUAGAACAACAGACACUACACAUCUGUCCUCCACAGAGGCUUUUUGUGUGUUUUAUCAUCUAAAAUCCAAUCCCUCGGUUUUUCUCUGUCAGUGCAGUUGCUAUGUUGCAGAAGAUCAACAGUAUCAGUGGCUGGAAAAGGUUUUUGGCUCUUGUCCAAGGAAGAACAUGCAGAUAACUAUUCUCACAUGUCGACAUGUUACCGAUUAUAAAACCUCAGAAUCCACCGGCAGCCUUCCUUCUCCUUUCCUGAGAGCCCUAAAAACACAGAAUUUCAAAGACUCGGCGUGUUGUCCAUUGCUAGAACAACCGAAUAUAGUACACGACCUUCCUGCAGCAGUUCUAAGCUACUGUCAAGUAUGGAAAAUCCCAGCAAUUCUGUACUUGUGUUAUACUGAUGUGAUGAAAUUAGACCUAAUCACAGUGGAAGCUUUUAAGCCUAUACUUUCUACCAGAAGCUUGAAGGGUUUGGUUAAGAAUAUUCCCCAAAGCACUGAGAUACUAAAGAAAUUGAUGACAACAAAUGAGAUUCAGAGUAACAUUUAUACAUGAUCUUAAACAUUGUUUUGUAGUGUAUAUUACUUGUCCAUUCCUUUAAGGGGAGCAGCCUGCACUCUUUUGUAGAUUACUUUUGGGGGAUAUAUUUUGAGAAUGAUGAAACGGAAUAAAAUUGUAAAAAAUUAAUUGUAGUUUUAAUUCCUUAUUUAUGGUGGUAUUAUUCACAACCAAAAUAAGCCAAGCAUUUUCCUUUUAUCCACUAGGUGGGAGUAUUGUUGUAUUUGAAUAUUUUAAGGUACUAUAGUUAAAUUUUUAUCUUAUUUAUUUAUUUAUUUAUUUUUUGAGGCUGGGUCUUGCUCUGUUGCCCAGGCUGAAGUGCAGUGUGCUAUCAUGGUUCACUGCAUCCUCGACCUCCUGGGCUCAAGCAUUUCCCCCGCCUCGGCCUCCCAAAAUGCUGGGAUUACAGGUGUGAGCCACUGUGCCCAACUUUAGUUAAAUUUUUCAAAGCUACAGAUAUCAGCAGAUGGUAUUCAUGUGGCAAAGUGUAGUUAAUUAGGUGUAACUAUUCAUUGACCUGUUGGUGAUUCUUAAUAUGUGGAAAGUUUCUGGAUAUUUUAGGAGUCCUGCAGUUUUUUUUAUCUUGUGGGUAAAAAUUGAUGACAAAGUAACAAAAUUAUAUAUUUACUAAAAAUGAAACAGAAAUGUGUAUGUCCUCACUUUUUAGUAAUAUCUGACAGAUAGCCUCUUCACCCAGACUUUCCCAGGGCUCUCUUUCAAGGCUGGCUCUGCGCGUGUCAGCAGUUCUCUUACAGUCAUGUGUUAUCAUUAGGAGUGUGAAUGGAAUCAUGAACCCGGAGUAGCCACACAACUUCACA